AGGCGGCUUCUUAGUCGUGGAGAGGGACGGUGGGGGUGACCCCCUCUCCUCUUGGCUUGACAGGAAGCAUGGCACUCUGGCGGGCAUACCAGCGGGCCCUGGCCGCUCACCCGUGGAAAGUACAGGUCCUGACAGCUGGCCUCCUGGACUGAAGGACACGCUUCCUGCUCCUCACUCCAAGAAGCCACUUCUUGCCCCUCUGCCUUCUGCGCAUGAAACUCAAAAGCCACAAAAGGUCCCUGAUGGGCCUGGGUGACAUUAUCUCACAGCAGCUGGUGGAGAGGCGGGGUCUGCAGGAACACCAGAGAGGCCGGACUCUGACCAUGGUGUCCCUGGGCUGUGGCUUUGUGGGCCCUGUGGUAGGAGGCUGGUACAAGGUUUUGGAUCGGUUCAUCCCUGGCACCACCAAAGUGGAUGCACUGAAGAAGAUGUUGUUGGAUCAGGGGGGCUUUGCCCCGUGUUUUCUAGGCUGCUUUCUCCCACUGGUAGGGGCACUUAAUGGACUGUCAGCCCAGGACAACUGGGCCAAACUACAGCGGGAUUAUCCUGAUGCCCUUAUCACCAACUACUAUCUAUGGCCUGCUGUGCAGUUAGCCAACUUCUACCUGGUCCCCCUUCAUUACAGGUUGGCCGUUGUCCAAUGUGUUGCUGUUAUCUGGAACUCCUACCUGUCCUGGAAGGCACAUCGGCUCUAAGCCUGCCUCACUCCAUCGUUUCCACCUUGCAGUGAUGCAGCUUGACCCUGGAACGGUCAGACAACCUCCUCAAAGUGGGCAUACCAGUUUCCACGGGGUUGGGUUGCCGGUCAGAGCUUAAGAGGACUAGCACCCUGCAAUGCCCCUCUUCACUCUAAAAUGUACACUGACUGCUUUAGAGCCCUUGAUAAUAGUCUUAUUCCCACCACAUACUAGGCACUCCAUAAAUAUCUGUUGAACCUUCAUGACCUUAUCAACUUUACACCCAUAUCCCAGCAAAUGCCACUCAUCCCCACUCUUCAUAGACACAUUUGUUACUCUAACCCUGCCUAGGCUUCUUGUAGCUCCAGCUCUUUAGAGACUCCCGGAACCCUUUAUAUGGUGCCUCAGUAAAUAUGUUAUUAAAUAUGUAAUCCGGAA